AAAUUCCAGUACAUUUGUUGAAUUUCUCAAAAACGUCUAACUAGAAUUUUAAUUGUGGUUGUACUCAAUUUAUAGACCAAUAUGGAGAAACUUGCUUUCUUUAUGUUGUUGAGUCUUCCUAUCCAUGAACUUCUCAUCUCUUUCAAUUUUUUUUUUUUUUUUUUGAGACAGAAUCUCACUUUGUUGCCCACACUGGAGUGCCGUGGUGUCAUCUUGGCUCACUGCAACCUCUGCCUCUUGGGUUCAAGUGAUUCUCCUGCCUCAGCCUCCCAAGUAGCUGGAAUUACAAGCACGUGCCACCAUGCCCAGCUAAUUUUUGUACUUUUAGUAGAGACAGGGUCUCACUGUGUUGGCCAAGCUGGUCUCGAACUCCUGACCUCAAAUGAUCCACCAGGCUUGGCCUCCCAAAGUGCUGGGAAUACAGGUGUGAGCCACCAUGCCUGGCCUCUCUCAAGUUAUUUGGGUACUUUAAAAUAUCCUAUGAUAAUUCUUAAAAAAUCAACUUUUUUGAAGUAUAAUUUGCACACAGUCCUGUAAAAUGCAGCCAUUUUUAUAGUUUAAGUUUUGACAGAUGUGUACACCUGUCUACAUGUAUAUAUACUUAUAUAACCACUACAAUAAAGAAAUAGAACUUUUUUUUUUUUUACCCAAAAUGCAUUCCUUUUGUCCUUCCAAGUCAUCCUCUGCCUUUAUCCCAGGCAGUCAUUGAUUUGCCUCCCAUCACUACAGAUUAGAUUUGUCUUUUCUAUGCUGUCAUAUAAAUGGAGCUAGGCAUUACUCUCUAUCUAGCUUCUUUUGCUUAGUGUAAUGUUUUAAGAUUCAUUCAUGUUGUUGCAUAUAUCAGCAGUCCAUUUUAUUGUUUAGUUUUGUACAGUUUUCGUGUGAACAUAUGUUUUUAUCUUUCUUGAGUAAGGAGAGGAAUUGAUAUGUCAUAUGGUAAGUAUAUGUUUAUAGGAAGCUACCAAGAUGUUUUCUAAAGUUGUAGUACUCCUACCAGCAAUGUGUGAGAUUUUUAGUUGCUCCAUAUCCUCAUGUUUCAUAUUGUCAGCCGUUUUAAUUUAGGUCAUUCUCCUGGGUAUGAGAUCAGGCAUUGCAAUAGCUCGUGUGUCAAAUCUGGCACAUCUGUUUUUGUUUUUUUCAUCCCCAUGGACACGAGGGAAACAUCUAUUUUUGUAAAUAGUUUUAUGUAUUAUCUAUGGCUACUUUACUUCUACAAAGCAGAGCUAAGUAGUUGCAACAGAGAUGACAUGGCCUGCAAACCCUAAUAUAUUUACUCUGUAUCUCCCUAUGGAAAAUGUUUACUGACCUCUGGAAUAGAGGUUUCUCAUUGUGGUUUUAAUUUGCAUUUCCCUGAUGACUAAUGAUGUUGAAUAUCUUUUAAUAUGUUUAUGGGCCAUUUGUAUAUCUUCUUUUUGGAGGUGUCUGUUGUAAUCUUUUGCUUAUUUUUUAUUUCAUAUAUUUUUUAUUCCUAGAACUUCCACUUGGUUUUUUAUAUUUUCUGUUUCUUAGAUGAAAUUGUCUAUUUUUUCCCCAUUCAUCCUCAUCGUAUUUUCCUUUACCUUAUUGAGUAUAGUUUUAAUAGCUUUUUAAAAUCCAUGUCUGAUAACGUCUGGGUCAUCUUGGGGUUGACAUCAGUUAACUGUCUUAUCCUUUGUGAUGAGACCACAUUUUUGUGGCUCUUGGUAUGUUGACUAAUUUAAGAUUGUAUACUGGACAUUGUGAAUGUUAUGUUUUGGAGACUGGUUUAUUUUAUAUUUAUCCAAAGGGUAUUUUUUUUUUGUUAGGAGGCAGUUAACUUGAUUAGACCCAUACCAAACCAUUAUGCCUGUGGUGGGAAAUGGCUUAGCUCUCAGUUCAUUUCUUGUUUUAGCUUUAAGCUGCUUCUAGUUUACUUGAGGCCAGGAAUUCAAGACCAGCCUGCACAACAUAGUUAGACUCAUAUCUCUAAAAAAAUUUUAAAAAUUAGCUGGGCAUAGUGGAGUGCACAUGCAUGGUUCAGAGAUAAGCUAUAGAUUUAGGCUGUUAAAAUACAGAAUAUAGGGGUUCCUUUCUGUGGCCCUCUCCUUUCUAGAGUCCCCCAUCACUCUCCUGCGUCAUCCCGCAUUAUCCUGGCCUUCUUUCCUGGUUCUUCUAGUUCCUCUGGCCAGAAAGAUGUCAGUCUUUCUACUGAAGUUGUAGCUGGUCCUGUGCCUUUGUGAUGGCGACCACAGCCACGUUUGGGCAAAGCUGCAAAAGUUGGGAUCUCAAUCUACAUGGAUCACUUACUCCCAGUUUGAUUCUCUUCUAAAAUGCAUCUGUAUUUCAGUCUCCAGAGUCCUCAGGUAGUUGUUUUUUGUGUGUGUUUUAUCCACAGAGCUUCCUUUUUAGGAGGACUGAUAUAUUGGGCUCUCACUCAUCCAUAUUUUUUGGUCCAUUUUAAAAUUGCAGUUUGGUUAUUUUUGAGUUGCAAGUGUGCUGUAUUUAUCCUGAGUAGAAGUAUGUGUCAGAUAAAAGUAUGAUGAAUGAUUUCUUCCAGUAUAUGGCUUGCCUUUUAAUUUCAUUAGUGUUUUUGAAGAGUAGAUGUUUUAAUUUUGAUGAAGCUUAAUUGAUCAUUUUUCUUUUAUGGUUGUGCUUUUUGAUGUCUUAUUUUUUAUUUUUAUUAUUUGAAUGGCCAGUUAAUAGAUUGAUGUCUUAUCUAAGAAAUCUUUGCCCAAGUUUGCAAAGAUUUUCUAUAUUUUAUUUUAGAAGUUUUAUAGGUUAGCUCCAUGUAGUGGAUUUAGAGGUUUUUUUUGCAUAUAAACUGAAGGUGAGAGUCAAAAUUAAUUUUUUGGUUAUGGAGUAUUCAGUUGCUGAAAGACUAUCCCAUCCUUAUUCUGACAUCUUUGUCAGAAUUCACUUGACCGUAUAUGUACAACUUUAAUUUUAGACUCUGUUCUGUCCACUGAUCUGUAUGUCUAUCCUUACACCCAAUACCAUGCACUUGAUUAUGAAUGUUUUAUAUUGUGUUGAAAACUUCCAACUUUGUUCUUUUCAAAAUUCUUUUGGUUAUCUUAGGUCUUUUGCAUUCUAGAAUAAUGUUUUACAAUCUGCUCAGUCCUUAUGGUUUUUGUUUCUUUCAUGAAUGAAUGCUUGAUUUCUAAGCAAAGCAAAAUUUUCUUGAUUUUUCUGAUGUUUUAUGAUCAAAGUUUCUUGGCAUAGCUAGAAGUUUGCUGUCUUUAUAAAUGUCAUGUCUUUUAAAAUACUUUGCUAACUUUGAUUUGGUAAUAUUUUAUAUAAAAUAUACAUAAAAUAUUUUGUGGGGUUAGAUAUGUAUGUAUUUUUAAAUCUCACAAAAUAUUAUACUCUCAAUCUUUGUUUACAUUUGCCUAUAUAUUUGUUGCUUUGUGUCAGAAGGUGUUUUUAUUUUGCCCUCAUUCUUUUUUUUUUUUUUUUUUUUUUGGGACGGAUUCUUGCUUUGUCACCCAGGCUGGAGUGCAGUGGUGCAAUCUGGGCUCAUUGCAACCUCCGCCUUCCGGAUUCAAGUGAUUUUUGUGCCUCAGCCUCCCAAAUCCUGGGAUUACAAGCAUGUGCCACCAUGCCUGGCUAAUUUUUGUAUUUUUAGUAAAGAUGGGGUUUUGCUAUGUUGGCCACCCCAGUCUUGAACUCCUGGCUUUAAGUGAUCUGCCCGCCUCAGCCUCCCAAAGUUCUGGGAUUACAGAUGUGAGCCACCAUGCCCGGCCUUCAUCCUCAUUCUUGAAAGACAUAUUUGCUGAGUACAGGAUUGUAUGUUGGUAGUUAUUUUUGUGUUGAAGAUACUAUUCCAUGUCUUCUGAUUAAAUUAUUGAUGUCAAAAUUAACUAUCAGUCUUAUUGUCCUUCUUUUGAAGGUAGUUUAUCUUUCUCCUUGGGCUACUUUUCUCCUUGUGUUUUCCCAGUUGCAUAAUGUGUCUUUGUGUGGAUUUCCUUUAUGUAUCCUGCUUGGGAUUUGUUGGACUUUUUGAAUCUUUGACUUGGUGUAUUUCAUUGGCUCUGUAAAAUUCUCAGCUAUUAUCUCUAGGUAUUUCCUUCCUCAUUCUUCUCUUGUUUUGGGAUUCUGAUUAAAUAGAUAUUAAGCCUCACUUUAUCCCCUAUGUCUGUUACGUUUUCUUUGUUGUUUUUCAUCUUUUUGUCUCUCCAUGAUGCUUUGCGGAUAAUUUCUUUUGCUCGGUCUUCUAGUUCACUGAUUCUCUCUUAUUUGUAUCUAACCUCCAGCUGUCUUAGUCCAUUCAGGCUACUUUAACAAAAUACAGUCAGCCUUCCAUAUCUGCAGGUUCUGCAUGUGUGGAUUCAAUCAACUGUAGAUGAGGAACCCGUGGAUAUGGAGGGCCGACUAUAUUACGCCAUUUUAUGUCAGGGACAUUUUAUGUAAUUCCUGAGAAUUUGGUAUAUGUGUGGGGGUGGGAGGGUGGGAUAUCCUUGAUCCAAUCCCCUGCAGGUACCAAGGGAUAAACUGUACCUUAGAUGGAGUAAUUUGUAAAUAAUAAAAAUUUAUUUCUCACGGUUCUGUAGGCUGGAAAUUUCAAGAUCAAGGUGCCAGCAGAUUCAGUGUCUGGUGAGGGUUGCUUUCUCUGUUUCAAAGAUGGCUACUUUUUGCUGUGUCCUCACAUGGCAGAAGGAGUAAACAUGGUCUCUCAUACCCUUUUGUAAGGGCCCUCUGAUCCUAUUCAUGAGGGUAGUGCUCUCAAGACCUAAUCAUCUCCUAGAGUCCUCGCUUCUUAAUACUAUCACACUGGUGAUUAAGUUUCAACAUACUAAUUUUGGAGGGAGACAUUCAGACCAUUGCAUUGUUCUUAAACUACGAGUUGAGCUUUAAGUUUUAAUUAUUUUUAGUUGAGUAAUUGUGCUUGAUCUUUUUCCGAUCUGCUCUGCUUUUUCCAGGAUCCUUUUUCUUACAAGUUUUUUAAAACUUUUGUUCCUUUAAAUAUAAUAAGCAUUGUAUUAUAGAAUUUGUGACUGAUCAUUCUAAGAUUUAAAGUCUCAGAUCUUUUAUUUCUCCUGAUUGUUGCUCAUGGUGUCUUAUUUUCUGUUUGUUUGGCUAUAAUGGAGGCCCCAAAUGAAGGCUUCUGCUACUAAAGAGGAUUUGUGUUUGCUUCAGUCAAAGAAAGAGAAAGUUGAAUUAAUUCUUUCAGCCUUCACUUUUGCCUUGAUUCGCUCAGCUUAUUUUGAGUUAGUCUCUGCAUUGUGCCAGCGCAUUCCACAGUUGAUGAAAGAGGAAGCAUCCAAAGUGAGCCCAUCAGUUCUACUUAGCAUUGAUGACAGUGACCCAAUUGUCUGCCCAGCUCUCUGGGAAGCUGUACUCUAUACACUUACAACUAUUGAGGACUGUUGGCUUCAUGUAAAUGCAAAAAAGAGUGUGUUUCCCAAGCUAUCAACUGUGAUUCGUGAAGGUGGUCGGGGUCUAGCUACUGUCAUAUAUCCUUACCUUCUGCCAUUCAUCAGCAAGCUCCCUCAGUCCAUCACAAAUCCAAAGUUGGAUUUCUUCAAAAAUUUCCUCACGUCUCUAGUUGCUGGGCUGUCAACAGAGAGAACUAAAACCAGCUCUUUAGAGUCCUCGGCAGUAAUAUCUGCUUUUUUUGAAUGCUUACGUUUUAUAAUGCAGCAAAACUUAGGUGAGGAAGAGAUUGAACAGAUGCUCGUCAAUGAUCAGUUGAUCCCUUUUAUUGAUGCAGUUCUCAAAGACCCAGGAUUGCAACAUGGGCAGCUAUUUAACCAUUUAGCAGAAACUCUAAGUUCCUGGGAAGCCAAAGCAGACACGGAAAAAGAUGAAAAAACAGCUCACAACUUGGAGAACGUACUGAUACAUUUCUGGGAAAGACUGUCAGAGAUCUGUGUUGCGAAAAUCAGUGAGCCAGAAGCUGAUGUUGAGUCCGUUUUGGGUGUAUCUAACCUAUUACAGGUGCUUCAGAAGCCGAAGAGCUCAUUGAAGUCAAGUAAAAAAAAAAAUGGUAAGGUUAGAUUUGCUGAUGAGAUACUUGAAAGCAAUAAAGAGAAUGAAAAAUGUGUAUCUUCAGAAGGAGAGAAGAUUGAAGGCUGGGAAUUAACAACUGAACCUUCUCUCACUCAUAAUUCUUCAGGCCUUUUGUCUCCUCUAAGGAAAAAACCUUUGGAAGACUUAGUCUGUAAACUCGCAGAUAUAAGUAUUAAUUAUGUCAAUGAACGAAAGUCAGAGCAACAUCUAAGGUUUCUUUCUACUCUGCUUGACUCCUUUUCUUCAAGCCGAGUAUUUAAAAUGCUACUUGGUGAUGAAAAACAGAGUAUUGUCCAAGCCAAACCUCUUGAAAUAGCCAAGCUUGUACAAAAAAAUCCUGCGGUGCAGUUUUUAUACCAGAAACUGAUAGGUUGGCUAAAUGAAGAUCAAAGGAAGGAUUUUGGUUUCCUGGUGGACAUUUUGUACAGUGCUCUCCGGUGCUGUGACAAUGAUAUGGAAAGAAAAAAAGUCUUGGAUGAUCUAACCAAGGUGGACUUGAAAUGGAAUUCUCUUCUUAAGAUUAUUGAAAAGGCAUGUCCUAGUUCAGAUAAACAUGCUUUAGUAACUCCUUGGCUCAAAGGCGAUAUCCUUGGUGAGAAAUUGGUCAACUUGGCAGAUUGUCUUUGUAAUGAGGACUUGGAAUCCAGGGUAUCUUCAGAAUCUCACUUCUCAGAAAGAUGGACUCUUCUAAGCUUGGUAUUAUCCCAACAUGUUAAAAAUGAUUACUUGAUUGGAGACGUAUAUGUUGAAAGAAUCAUUGUUAGACUUCAUGAAACUUUAUUCAAAACAAAGAAAUUAUCAGAAGCUGAAAGCAGUGACUCAUCAGUGUCUUUUAUCUGUGAUGUGGCCUAUAACUAUUUCAGCUCAGCGAAAGGAUGCUUGCUAAUGCCAUCAUCUGAAGAUUUAUUAUUAACUCUCUUUCAGUUAUGUGCUCAGAGCAAAGAAAAAACACAUUUGCCAGAUUUUCUUAUCUGUAAACUGAAAAAUACUUGGCUCUCUGGUGUAAAUUUAUUGGUUCAUCAAACUGACAGUUCAUAUAAAGAGAGUACCUUCCUACAUUUGUCUGCUCUGUGGCUGAAGAACCAAGUUCAGGCUUCAUCUUUGGAUAUCAACAGUCUCCAAGUCCUCUUGUCUGCUGUUGAUGAUUUGCUAAAUACACUUCUAGAGAGUGAAGAUUCUUAUCUUAUGGGAGUUUAUAUUGGAAGUGUAAUGCCGAACGACAGUGAAUGGGAAAAGAUGAGGCAGUCUCUUCCUAUGCAGUGGUUACAUAGACCUCUUUUAGAGGGAAGAUUGAGUUUGAAUUAUGAAUGUUUCAAAACAGAUUUUAAGGAACAGGACAUAAAGACACUUCCCAGCCAUUUGUGUACUUCAGCAUUAUUGAGCAAAAUGGUCUUAAUUGCACUGAGAAAGGAAACAGUCUUAGAAAAUAAUGAGCUUGAGAAAAUAAUUGCAGAACUGCUUUAUUCACUGCAGUGGUGUGAAGAAUUAGAUAACCCACCUAUUUUUCUAAUUGGAUUUUGUGAAAUACUUCAAAAAAUGAAUAUUACGUAUGAUAACUUACGUGUACUUGGUAAUACGUCGGGCCUUUUGCAGCUGUUAUUUAACAGGUCCAGAGAACAUGGCACACUGUGGUCUCUUAUUAUUGCUAAGUUGAUCCUUUCCCGAAGCAUUUCAUCUGAUGAAGUAAAACCACAUUAUAAGAGAAAAGAAAGUUUUUUUCCACUAACUGAAGGCAAUUUGCAUACCAUUCAAAGUCUAUGUCCAUUUUUGUCAAAAGAAGAAAAGAAAGAAUUUAGUGCUCAAUGUAUACCUGCUCUUUUGGGCUGGACUAAGAAAGAUCUUUGCAGCACUAAUGGAGGUUUUGGACAUCUUGCCAUUUUCAAUUCUUGUCUGCAAACCAAAAGUAUAGAUGAUGGAGAGCUAUUACAUGGAAUAUUAAAAAUCAUAAUAUCCUGGAAGAAAGAGCAUGAAGAUAUUUUUCUUUUCAGUUGUAAUCUAUCAGAAGCAAGUCCAGAGGUACUGGGUGUAAAUAUAGAAAUAAUCCGGUUUCUUUCCCUAUUUCUGAAAUACUGCUCAUCCCCUUUGGCAGAGAGUGAGUGGGACUUCAUCAUGUGCUCCAUGUUGGCUUGGUUGGAGACAACAAGUGAGAAUCAGGCAUUGUAUUCUAUUCCACUUGUGCAACUGUUUGCCUGUGUCAGCUGUGAUUUGGCCUGUGACCUCAGUGCUUUCUUUGAUUCCACAACUCUGGAUACCAUUGGCAAUCUUCCUGUAAAUCUAAUCAGUGAAUGGAAAGAAUUUUUUUCCCAAGGCAUCCACAGUUUGCUUUUACCUAUUUUGGUGACUGUUACAGGAGAAAACAAAGAUGUGUCUGAAACAUCCUUUCAGAAUGCAAUGCUGAAACCCAUGUGUGAAACAUUAACGUAUAUCUCAAAGGAACAGCUAUUGAGUCACAAACUUCCUGCAAGAUUAGUUGCUGACCAAAAAACAAACUUACCAGAAUAUCUCCAGACUUUGUUAAAUACAUUGGCCCCAUUACUCCUCUUCAGAGCUAGGCCUGUGCAAAUUGCUGUUUAUCAUAUGCUAUACAAAUUGAUGCCUGAAUUACCACAGUAUGAUCAGGAUAAUCUAAAGUCAUACGGAGAUGAAGAAGAAGAGCCAGCCUUGUCACCACCAGCAGCACUGAUGUCUCUUCUUAGCAUUCAAGAGGACUUACUAGAAAAUGUUUUGGGGUGUAUUCCUGUUGGACAGAUAGUUACUAUUAAACCACUGAGUGAAGACUUCUGUUAUGUUCUGGGAUACCUUCUCACUUGGAAAUUAAUACUAACUUUCUUCAAAGCUGCAUCAUCACAGCUUCGGGCUUUGUAUUCCAUGUAUCUUCGGAAAACAAAGAGUUUGAAUAAAUUGCUCUAUCACCUGUUCAGGCUUAUGCCAGAAAAUCCAACCUAUGCAGAGACAGCAGUUGAGGUCCCAAAUAAGGACCCUAAAACAUUCUUUACUGAGGAGCUCCAGCUGAGUAUUAGAGAAACAACAAUGCUUCCAUACCACAUUCCACACUUGGCUUGUUCAGUCUAUCAUAUGACAUUAAAAGACUUGCCUGCCAUGGUUAGGUUGUGGUGGAAUAGCAGUGAGAAGCGUGUUUUCAAUAUUGUGGAUAGAUUUACAAGCAAGUAUGUCAGCAGUGUUCUUUCUUUUCAAGAAAUAUCUUCUGUACAAACAAGUACACAACUAUUUAAUGGCAUGACGGUUAAAGCUCGAGCUACUACUCGAGAGGUAAUGGCUACUUAUACUAUUGAGGACAUAGUUAUUGAACUUAUAAUACAACUGCCUUCAAAUUAUCCACUGGGUUCAAUAAUAGUAGAAAGUGGGAAAAGAGUAGGAGUAGCUGUUCAGCAGUGGCGGAACUGGAUGCUGCAGUUAAGCACUUACCUCACCCAUCAGAAUGGAAGUAUUAUGGAAGGCUUAGCUUUAUGGAAAAAUAACGUAGACAAACGUUUUGAGGGUGUUGAAGAUUGCAUGAUCUGUUUCUCAGUCAUUCACGGUUUCAACUAUUCCCUUCCCAAAAAAGCCUGUAGAACAUGCAAGAAAAAAUUCCAUUCAGCCUGCUUGUACAAAUGGUUUACAUCUAGCAACAAAUCCACUUGUCCACUGUGUCGUGAGACGUUUUUCUGAGAUUUUUUUCACUGGAAGGGAUCCCUGAAGUACAUCAAACAAAGGCAUUGGAUUUGGAUCCGUCUGAAAGUGUGGAUGUGGGGAAGCCAGUGAGCAUUACUUUUAAAUAGGACCUUCUCUGGAAAAUUAUUUUGGUUAAUGUAAUAAUCCUAAAAUCAGGUUUACUUAACUUUAGAUUGCUUUGUAAAUGUUUGGAAACUUUCUUUUACAAAAGAAUAUUACAUAUUUGAGAGAAAAUAUUUCUAUUAAUGGUUUAAUUUCUUUGUAUAUUUAAAAAUAAAUAUGAAAAACCCCUAAAUUACAGAAUUGGAAUUUGUGAAAAGAUUGCACAACUAUAUUAUUGAUAAACCCAUUCCGUUUGUUGAUCUGUGUUUUAGAAUAGUCCAAGUGAAGCAAAACGAACUGAGAGAGCUGAUUUACAUCUAUAGAUAUUUUAAGCCUUAUUUAUUAGUUAUGACAAUAAAUUAGUAUUCUGAUAUUUGUAGAUUAUUUUAAUGAUAAAAAUGACACUAAGCUAUUAAUACGGCUUGUCUUAAGAUAUCUGGAGGCAUGCUCUGAAAUCCUAUAUAAAAGAGUUUAAACUGAACUUUAAGGUGCCUCCAUUUAUCAAGGGUUAUGAAACUCAGAAAAUUAAAUUCUUGAUGCUGACCUUUUUGCUUGUGGGAGAAUUAUUUCUAUAUAUUAGUGAAAUUUGAAUUGUAAACUUGUCAGUGAAUUUAUCACUCUGAGCGAGUCUCUAGAGGGUGAGAAUUUGAGAGAAAUAGUAAUUUGAUUAUUUCAUUCAUGAAGCGGAGUGGUAGUUAUCCUUCUAUUGAGAGGGAAGAAAUAAAUGAGUAUUACUGAAACUUAAAGAUCAGUGGAAAAAAAAAACAUUUAAAAAUGUUGUAGGAGACUUUCAAUUUUGGAAGCAAACUGAGCUAUUCUUACCAGCCAAAGUUAUACUAAAUAAGAGACUUGGGGGAGCAAAUGUUUUUCAGCCUUCAGAAAUGAAAGUUAAGGAUUUUAGCACUAGGUAAAAUUCAGUAUAAUAGGCUGAAGUGGAGUAAGUGAAAACCUGCCUUUUGCCACUCUUAAAAAUUGUGCCCAAAAUAUAAAAGUGUGGAACUUUAGAACUUGGAAUAAUUUUAUUGCAGUCUUCCAUUACAUGGAAAUAGCAUAUCUAAUAUCUAGGUUACUUGAGAGACCAGCUAAUCAUCUCUGUUGCACAUGUUUAAUUGGCAAAAAGCAAUUCAUGAUAAAUAAAAUUACUGCUUUCCAUCUACUGGGUAAAAUGACUAUUGAAAUAGUAUGAAUGUGGUCAGAGGAUUAUAGUUGAGAGUGAAGUACUAUGUGUGAGUUAUAGAUCUCUCGAAUUAUAUUUAUAGAUGCAGUGUCCUGCCCAGUUUUGUUUGCCUCCUACAUUUUACUGUAAAAUAUUUAUUGUCUUCUAGCCUUGAGCCUCUGAGGGUCAGUAAGUGAAGUACAGAUAGCAAAAUUUUACUACCUCGUUAACCCUUUUCUUAAAAUAUUCUCUAUCUUUCUAUGUCUCUUUCUGACAUAGUAAUCCCAAAGGAUUGUGUUACUCCCCGUGAAAGUUAUUACUUUUCCUUUAAAAAUGGUUUUAUAAUAAGACUGUUUAAAACCUUUCCAGUAUUGGUACAUCUUGGCUUCUGGCCCAAACCCCAAGCAGAAAAGAAAAUGGAAUAAUGGAGCAUUGUUUUUCCACAUUAGUAUUAGGGCAUCAGAUUCUUGGUGAAACACUAUAAUUAAGUAGUUAUAAUUAAAUAACUGUUCUUCAUACUUAGGACUCUUAAUACAUUUCUUUAAGACUUGUAAGUAUAAUUGUAAAGCUUGUUAACUGUUUAUAUACUAAAGAAAAAGCUUUACAAGAUAAGACUGAAAUUCAGAAUACCACAUCUGUACAGCGUUGACAACUCUAACUAAAAGGAUUACAGCCCUUAAAAUUUUAGCUUAAGGACAUUUUAAAAUUGCAUGAGAUUAGCAAAAUUAUUAAUUUAAAACCCCAAAGUAAAUUGCAAAUUUUAAAAUUUAUUUUUGACUCUUUUAUCACAUGCUCCAAUGUAUGUACAUAAGUGUCUGUGGCUUAAAUAAUAUGUUGUUAUUUGAUACAUUUUUGUGGUGCAAGUAAUUAAUGUUAUUAUUUGAUUGUUAUACCAUAUGUGCCCAUUAAAAUUCUUUUUAAUUAAAAAUAUUUCAAAUAUGCAGAAAAAUAAUAAUAUAAAUGCCCUUGUACCCUUCACAUACUAUUUUGCCAUAUUUGCUUCUGAUUUUUAAAUAAAUAAAAUGUUACUCUUUUGUACUUCU